GAAGUGAAUCUAGCUCUGAAGGCAUGGCGCGUACGAAGCAGACUGCUCGCAAGUCCACCGGCGGCAAGGCUCCGCGCAAGCAGCUGGCCACCAAGGCGGCUCGGAAGAGCGCUCCGGCCACCGGCGGUGUCAAGAAGCCCCAUCGCUAUCGGCCUGGUACAGUGGCUCUCCGCGAGAUUCGCCGCUACCAGAAGUCCACCGAGCUGCUGAUCAGAAAGCUGCCUUUUCAGCGUCUGGUGCGUGAGAUCGCGCAGGACUUCAAGACCGACUUGCGCUUCCAGAGCUCCGCGGUGAUGGCGCUGCAAGAGGCAUGCGAGGCCUACCUGGUGGGGCUCUUUGAGGACACCAACCUGUGCGCCAUCCACGCCAAGCGGGUGACUAUCAUGCCCAAGGACAUCCAGCUCGCACGUCGUAUCCGCGGCGAGAGGGCUUGAGUCUCAAGGACUCACUGAUUACAUACCCAAAGGCUCUUUUCAGAGCCACCCA